GUCGUCUCCCGGCAGUGCAGCUGCCGCUACCGCCGCCCUCUGCCCGCCGGCCCGUCUGUCUACCCCCAGCAUGAGCGGCCUGCGCGUCUACAGCACGUCGGUCACCGGCUCCCGCGAAAUCAAGUCCCAGCAGAGCGAGGUGACCCGAAUCCUGGAUGGGAAGCGCAUCCAAUACCAGCUAGUGGACAUCUCCCAGGACAACGCCCUGAGGGAUGAGAUGCGAGCCUUGGCAGGCAACCCCAAGGCCACCCCACCCCAGAUUGUCAACGGGGACCAGUACUGUGGGGACUAUGAGCUCUUCGUGGAGGCUGUGGAACAAAACACGCUGCAGGAGUUCCUGAAGCUGGCUUGAGUCAAGCCUGUCCAGAGUUCCCCUGCUGGACUCCAUCACCACACUCCCCCCAGCCUUCACCUGGCCAUGAAGGACCUUUUGACCAACUCCCUGUCAUUCCUAACCUAACCUUAGAGUCCCUCCCCCAAUGCAGGCCACUUCUCCUCCCUCCUCUCUAAAUGUAGUCCCCUCUCCUCCAUCUAAAGGCAACAUUCCUUACCCAUUAGUCUCAGAAAUUGUCUUAAGCAACAGCCCCAAAUGCUGGCUGCCCCCAGCCAAGCAUUGGGGCCGCCAUCCUGCCUGGCACUGGCUGAUGGGCACCUCUGUUGGUUCCAUCAGCCAGAGCUCUGCCAAAGGCCCCGCAGUCCCUCUCCCAGGAGGACCCUAGAGGCAAUUAAAUGAUGUCCUGUUCCAUUGGCA